AAGACAAGCGGGCAUUGGCCACAGCAGCGCGAGGCGGGCACGGGGUAUUGUCCGGCUCCGGCGGCGGCGGUCGGUGCUGCGAGAGCGGCGGCGGCGGCGCGGGUCGGCAGCGGGAGGGCGCGCGGCCGAGCGGAGGCGGAGUCGGCGCCGAGAACAUGGCUGGAGGCAAAGCUGGAAAGGACAGUGGGAAGGCCAAGGCUAAGGCAGUAUCUCGCUCACAGAGAGCUGGGCUACAGUUUCCUGUGGGCCGCAUCCACAGACACUUGAAGACUCGCACCACAAGCCAUGGAAGGGUGGGUGCCACUGCUGCCGUGUACAGUGCUGCGAUUCUGGAGUACCUCACUGCAGAGGUGCUGGAGCUGGCAGGUAAUGCUUCUAAGGAUCUCAAAGUAAAGCGUAUCACUCCGCGUCACUUGCAGCUUGCAAUCCGUGGUGAUGAAGAGUUGGAUUCUCUUAUCAAGGCUACCAUAGCUGGGGGUGAGAAGAGAAGGUGUUCUUAGAUCAGAAGAUGCCAUUGUAUUAGGUGACGGCAAGGUUUUGCUGAUUUAGUGGAACAAGAUUCUACUGGGAUGUGUGCUGAGCUGAACCAAGGAACUGCCCGAAUGUGCUGAACAAGGACAUUUGCUUCUCAGAUACGUGAAUUCAAUUUUAAGCAAGAUUCUUGAUCUGCUUCAGAGCAGCUUUGAUUUAAAGUAAUUUCAGAGCGCUUUUCCUUGCAUGAGUAAUUUUCUGAAUGUAUAAAAUAUUCUAUUUAUGUUUGACCUUUUGGAUAAACUGUGUUGCUGCAGUGUUGGUCCACACUACCAUCCUAAGUGAAGACUUAGUAAGUCUGAGGAUCUCCAGGCACUGGAAAGAGUGAGAACCUGGGAGUGAAAGGGUUAUAGUUAGUGUUCAUUUUUCGGGUUUUGUUUCAUAGGGAGUCCUGAGUGGGGUAACCUGAAAUGUUUUAACAGUUGAAGAUCAUCCUAUUCCUAUCCCCAGUAAAAAUAGGCCUUUCCACAAUCUUCUACCAGUUAACUUAGCUUUUUUUUUUUUUUUUUCCUUUAAUAGAGUCUCAUUCUUGUCACCCAGACUGGAGUGCGAUGGCACGAUCUUGGCUCACUGCAACCCUCCCUCCCGGGUUCCAGCGAUUCUCCUGCCUCAGCCUCCCAAGUAGCUGGGAUUACAGGCGCACGCCACCAUGCCCAGCUAAUUUUUGUAUUUUUAGUAGACGUGGGGUUUCACCAUGUUGGCCAGACUGGUCUCAAACUCCUGACCUCAGGCGAUCCGCCCGUCUAAGCCUUCCAAAGUGCUGGGAUUACUGGCAGGAACCACCAGGCCCAGCCAACCAGCAUUUCUUAAGGUGAAAAUACAUGGUGUUAAUUUAUAUUUUGAGUGAGACCCAGUCCAGCUGCUAUAACUGCUUGGACACUUGGCAGAGGACAGAGUACUGCAAAAGUGUCUAAGGGAGACAGCAUUUUGCCUUGGGUGCUGUAGAUGUACAAGAGAGGUUCCAGGAGGGGGUGAUAGGCAGAAUUUUGGUCCCCAUCACCUUCCCUGCCCAGUGUUAUGCCUAUGAAUGUGUUACAUUAUGUGGUAAAAGGGACUUUGCAGAUGUAACUAAAAUUUCUAAAAUAGAGAUAUUAUCCUGGAUUACCUGGGGGAACCCAGUGUAAUUACAUGAACCCUUAAAAAUGGAAGAGGAUGCAGGAGUCAGAUUCAAAGGAAGGCCCAAGGUGCUAUUGCUGACUUGAAGAUAGAGGGGCCAUGUGGAAAUCAAGAGAAGGAAGUGAAUCCUUCCAGUGAGCUUGGAAGAAAGCACCUUGAGGCACAGAUGAGAAGCUUGGCCUUACCUGAUGCCUUGAUUUUAGCCUGGUGAGACCCUGAGCAUAUAAAUUUGCUGUGCUAUGCCACACUUCUCACCUACAGAAACUUAGUUUAAAGCCACUAAGUUUGUGGUAAUUUGUUGGCUUUAGGCCCCUGAGGGUAGAGAUUUAUGGCUUGUGUUACAAGUAGAGAGCAGUGGAGAGUUGGGCUUUGUAAUUCUUUCAAGGGUGAUUGUAGUUCUGGAGUCCUAUCUACCUGGGUUCAGAUCUUUGUUGGCCAGUCCCUGGCUGUGUGACUUCACUGCUUUAAGCCUCUGUCUUCAUCCUUAAAGUGGUGAUGAUAGUACCUACCUCACUCUGAUCUCUGAAUGAGAACACAUGUAAGACACUUAGCACAGUUCCUGGUGCUCAAAGAGUUCCAACACCUGAAAGCACCAUGGCCCUGUUUGUUUUUCAGUCAAGAUUUCUAAAAGCCGUUAUUACCAGAGGUUCAGUGAGAACAUGGGCAGGGUAAACUCAAAAUGGAGAACAUAAAAACUGGGACUCCCAGACCAGUCACUUAGAAGACUGCUGCAGGAAGUACCAAGGUCGUUAAGAAUCAGUAAUAAUAAUAAGUAAUGUGUGAAUCCAUUAGAAUGUUGAGAAGUAGACCUUUGACAUUUCAGAAAAAUGUAUAUCUCAGACACAGCCAUAUGUAUUGUUAUCCCUGAGUUGGAAGAGCAUCACAGGGCAUAGUUUCACAAAAGCUUCAAAAAAUAUACUAAUUGCUGGUAAUAUGUGAACUAACAGAAAAAAAUAGCCAUGUUAAAAUAGGAGUGCCUGACAAUUAGCUCUAUUCAUCUUGUCUCCUAGCUGUAAGCACCCUAGAUUCAAAUUAUGCACCUAGAAAACUAAAUUACUAUGUAUGUUAUAGGCCUUUGAAAUGGAUACAUGAAAAUUAGUGAAAUCAGAAUGAACGUUUCGCCUGCCAAAGAUAUGUAUUUUUAUAAGUGAUACAAGGGCCCCAUGAGCUCCAUGGCCACAUCUGUACAAAACAGGCCCUCCUUUCAGGAACUGGUCUCGAGAGAGCAAAGGGGUCAACUCCCUAAAUGGCAGCUGAGACAGUCCUCCCUGGUGGCAUGGCCCUGUUUCCUGUUGAUAUGGUGAUAGUUGGAGAGUCAAAUUUUUACCAGAAUUUGUGAAUAUCAUCUCUGGUUAAUGAUUACACAAAACCUUUUAAAAUUUUAAAAAAUUAUUUCUAAUUCUAUAAAUAAACUCUGCAGUUGUACAGCCACUGUACAGCUAACAUCUCAACACUGGAAAUGAGGCUGGUUUCUUCCAGUUUGGCUCAGAUUCUUCAGGGAAGCCCAGUUAAGACAAACAGCUCUCUAUACUCAAUCCUUACUUUGCUGAGAAGAUACAGGCCUGCCCACUCGCUCCCACCUGCUCUUCACGAGGAGUCCUUUAUUCCUGCAUGUUUCCUGUUCUUUGGGACCUUUAGGAGCUAACCUCCACAGAUGCUGAUAGUCUGUAGAGUCAGGAAUACCAUGUAACAUGUUGAAGUAGACUAAAGAUUAGUUCUUUGGCAAUAGCCCAGUCUGGACUUACUAUGUACUUUUGAAAAUAAAACUGCUUAUUUGUAAACUCUGUAAUUAGGACCUUUUGCUAUUUGAGUUAUAUUCCUUUCUAACUUCAAACGUCUGCAUUCAUGUAUAAUAGCCAUUUUAUGCACAGAUGAGGUGAUUCCCACACUUUUUUUCGCAGAUGUUUCAUUAUCUGGAUGAGUGUAUUACAUAAUAAAUUUGAAUAAUGGUAGUCUUCCAAAUGACAAAAAGCAAGCUAGUUGAUUUGUCAAUUUUGAGUUUAAAUGUUUUGACUGCUUAUCAGCAAAAAAAAUCAAAGAAUAGCAUACUAAUAUUAAUGGAAAUGCAGAGUAUAUUUAAUUGGCAUGAUUUUUUCAUGGAUGUGUGC